ACAAUUACUCUACAGCUCAGAACACCAACUGCUGAGGCUGCCUUGGGAAGAGGAUGAUCCUAAACAAAGCUCUGCUGCUGGGGGCCCUCGCUCUGACCACCGUGAUGAGCCCCUGUGGAGGUGAAGACAUUGUGGCUGACCACGUUGCCUCUUGUGGUGUAAACUUGUACCAGUUUUACGGUCCCUCUGGCCAGUACACCCAUGAAUUUGAUGGAGAUGAGCAGUUCUACGUGGACCUGGAGAGGAAGGAGACUGCCUGGCGGUGGCCUGAGUUCAGCAAAUUUGGAGGUUUUGACCCGCAGGGUGCACUGAGAAACAUGGCUGUGGCAAAACACAACUUGAACAUCAUGAUUAAACGCUACAACUCUACCGCUGCUACCAAUGAGGUUCCUGAGGUCACAGUGUUUUCCAAGUCUCCCGUGACACUGGGUCAGCCCAACACCCUCAUUUGUCUUGUGGACAACAUCUUUCCUCCUGUGGUCAACAUCACAUGGCUGAGCAAUGGGCAGUCAGUCACAGAAGGUGUUUCUGAGACCAGCUUCCUCUCCAAGAGUGAUCAUUCCUUCUUCAAGAUCAGUUACCUCACCUUCCUCCCUUCUGCUGAUGAGAUUUAUGACUGCAAGGUGGAGCACUGGGGCCUGGACCAGCCUCUUCUGAAACACUGGGAGCCUGAGAUUCCAGCCCCUAUGUCAGAGCUCACAGAGACUGUGGUCUGUGCCCUGGGGUUGUCUGUGGGCCUCAUGGGCAUUGUGGUGGGCACUGUCUUCAUCAUCCAAGGCCUGCGUUCAGUUGGUGCUUCCAGACACCAAGGGCCAUUGUGAAUCCCAUCCUGGAAGGGAAGGUGCAUCGCCAUCUACAGGAGCAGAAGAAUGGACUUGCUAAAUGACCUAGCACUAUUCUCUGGCCCGAUUUAUCAUAUCCCUUUUCUCCUCCAAAUAUUUCUCCUCUCACCUUUUCUCUGGGACUUAAGCUGCUAUAUCCCCUCAGAGCUCACAAAUGCCUUUACAUUCUUUCCCUGACCUCCUGAUUUUUUUUUUCUUUUCUCAAAUGUUACCUACAAAGACAUGCCUGGGGUAAGCCACCCGGCUACCUAAUUCCUCAGUAACCUCCAUCUAAAAUCUCCAAGGAAGCAAUAAAUUCCUUUUAUGAGAUCUAUGUCAAAUUUUUCCAUCUUUCAUCCAGGGCUGACUGAAACUAUGGCUAAUAAUUGGGGUACUCUUAUGUUUCAAUCCAAUUUAACCUCAUUUCCCAGAUCAUUUUUCAUGUCCAGUAACACAGAAGCCACCAAGUACAGUAUAGCCUGAUAAUAUGUUGAUUUCUUAGCUGACAUUAAUAUUUCUUGCUUCCUUGUGUUCCCACCCUUGGCACUGCCACCCACCCCUCAAUUCAGGCAACAAUGAAAUUAAUGGAUACCGUCUGCCCUUGGCCCAGAAUUGUUAUAGCAAAAAUUUUAGAACCAAAAAAUAAGUCUGUACUAAUUUCAAUGUGGCUUUUAAAAGUAUGACAGAGAAAUAAGUUAGGAUAAAGGAAAUUUGAAUCUCAAAAAUAUCAAAAGUAAAAAUGUAUUCUCAAAA